GGAGAGUGGGCUGGAGGCCGGGGCGGGACGCGUUGUGCAGCGGGUAAGCGCACGGCCGAGCGAGCAUGGAGGGGGACCGGGUGGCCGGGCGGCCGGUGCUGUCGUCGUUACCAGUGCUACUGCUGCUGCCGUUGCUAAUGUUGCGGGCCGCGGCGCUGCACCCAGACGAGCUCUUCCCACACGGGGAGUCGUGGGGGGACCAGCUCCUGCAGGAAGGCGACGACGAAAGCUCAGCCGUGGUGAAGCUGGCGAAUCCCCUGCACUUCUACGAAGCCCGAUUCAGCAACCUCUACGUGGGCACCAACGGCAUCAUCUCCACUCAGGACUUCCCCAGGGAAACGCAGUAUGUGGACUAUGAUUUCCCCACCGACUUCCCGGCCAUCGCCCCUUUUCUGGCGGACAUCGACACGAGCCACGGCAGAGGCCGAGUCCUGUACCGAGAGGACACCUCCCCCGCAGUGCUGGGCCUGGCCGCCCGCUAUGUGCGCGCUGGCUUCCCGCGCUCUGCGCGCUUUACCCCCACCCACGCCUUCCUGGCCACCUGGGAGCAGGUAGGCGCUUACGAGGAGGUCAAGCGCGGGGCGCUGCCCUCGGGAGAGCUGAACACUUUCCAGGCAGUUUUGGCAUCUGAUGGGUCUGAUAGCUACGCCCUCUUUCUUUAUCCUGCCAACGGCCUGCAGUUCCUUGGAACCCGCCCCAAAGAGUCUUACAAUGUCCAGCUUCAGCUUCCAGCUCGGGUGGGCUUCUGCCGAGGGGAGGCUGAUGAUCUGAAGUCAGAAGGACCAUAUUUCAGCUUGACUAGCACUGAACAGUCUGUGAAAAAUCUCUAUCAACUAAGCAACCUGGGGAUCCCUGGAGUGUGGGCUUUCCAUAUCGGCAGCACUUCCCCGUUGGACAAUGUCAGGCCAGCUGCAGUUGGAGACCUUUCCGCUGCCCACUCUUCUGUUCCCCUGGGACGUUCCUUCAGCCAUGCUACAGCCCUGGAAAGUGACUAUAAUGAGGACAAUUUGGAUUACUAUGAUGUGAAUGAGGAGGAAGCUGAAUACCUUCCGGGUGAACCAGAGGAGGCAUUGAAUGGCCACAGCAGCAUUGAUGUUUCCUUCCAAUCCAAAGUGGAUACAAAGCCUUUAGAGGGUAGGAUCUCCCCUCCAGAUUCUGAUCUGUCCUCCCCCUUGCAUCCAACACCUACUUAUUGGCCAUUCUAUCCUGAAACAGAAUCUUCCACCUUGGAUCCUCACACCAAAGAAGGAACAUCUCUGGGAGAGGUAGGGGGCCCAGAUUUAAAAGGCCAAGUUGAGCCCUGGGAUGAGAGAGAGACCAGAAGCCCAGCUCCACCAGAGGUAGACAGAGAUUCACUGGCUCCUUCCUGGGAAACCCCACCACCGUACCCCGAAAACGGAAGCAUCCAGCCCUACCCAGAUGGAGGGCCAGUGCCUUCGGAAAUGGAUGUUCCCCCAGCUCAUCCUGAAGAAGAAAUUGUUCUUCGAAGUUACCCUGCUUCAGGUCACACUACACCCUUAAGUCGAGGGACGUAUGAGGUGGGACUGGAAGACAACAUAGGUUCCAACACCGAGGUCUUCACGUAUAAUGCUGCCAACAAGGAAACCUGUGAACACAACCACAGACAAUGCUCCCGGCAUGCCUUCUGCACGGACUAUGCCACUGGCUUCUGCUGCCACUGCCAAUCCAAGUUUUAUGGAAAUGGGAAGCACUGUCUGCCUGAAGGGGCACCUCACCGAGUGAAUGGGAAAGUGAGUGGCCACCUCCACGUGGGCCAUACACCCGUGCACUUCACUGAUGUGGACCUGCAUGCGUAUAUCGUGGGCAAUGAUGGCAGAGCCUACACGGCCAUCAGCCACAUCCCACAGCCAGCAGCCCAGGCCCUCCUCCCCCUCACACCAAUUGGAGGCCUGUUUGGCUGGCUCUUUGCUUUAGAAAAACCUGGCUCUGAGAACGGCUUCAGCCUCGCAGGUGCUGCCUUUACCCAUGACAUGGAAGUUACAUUCUACCCGGGAGAGGAGACGGUUCGUAUCACUCAAACUGCUGAGGGACUUGACCCAGAGAACUACCUGAGCAUUAAGACCAACAUUCAAGGCCAGGUGCCUUACGUCUCAGCAAAUUUCACAGCCCACAUCUCUCCCUACAAGGAGCUGUACCACUACUCCGACUCCACUGUGACCUCUACAAGUUCCAGAGACUACUCUCUGACUUUUGGUGCAAUCAACCAAACAUGGUCCUACCGCAUCCACCAGAACAUCACUUACCAGGUGUGCAGGCACGCCCCCAGACACCCGUCCUUCCCCACCACCCAGCAGCUGAACGUGGACCGGGUCUUUGCCUUGUAUAAUGACGAAGAAAGAGUGCUUAGAUUUGCUGUGACCAAUCAAAUUGGCCCGGUCAAAGAGGAUUCAGACCCCACUCCGGGGAAUCCUUGCUAUGAUGGGAGCCACAUGUGUGACACAACAGCACGGUGCCAUCCAGGGACAGGUGUAGAUUACACCUGUGAGUGCGCAUCUGGGUACCAGGGAGAUGGACGGAACUGUGUGGAUGAAAAUGAAUGUGCAACUGGCUUUCAUCGCUGUGGCCCCAACUCUGUAUGUAUCAACUUGCCUGGAAGCUACAGGUGUGAGUGCCGGAGUGGUUAUGAGUUUGCAGAUGACCGGCAUACUUGCAUCUUGAUCACCCCACCUGCCAACCCCUGUGAGGAUGGCAGUCAUACCUGUGCUCCUGCUGGGCAGGCCCGGUGUGUUCACCAUGGAGGCAGCACGUUCAGCUGUGCCUGCCUGCCUGGUUAUGCCGGCGAUGGGCACCAGUGCACUGAUGUAGAUGAAUGCUCAGAAAACAGAUGUCACCCUGCAGCUACCUGCUACAAUACUCCUGGUUCCUUCUCCUGCCGUUGUCAACCCGGAUAUUAUGGGGAUGGAUUUCAGUGCAUACCUGACUCCACCUCAAGCCUGACACCCUGUGAACAACAGCAGCGCCAUGCCCAGGCCCAGUAUGCCUACCCUGGGGCCCGGUUCCACAUCCCCCAAUGCGACGAGCAGGGCAACUUCCUGCCCCUACAGUGUCAUGGCAGCACUGGUUUCUGCUGGUGCGUGGACCCUGAUGGUCAUGAAGUUCCUGGUACCCAGACUCCACCUGGCUCCACCCCGCCUCACUGUGGACCAUCACCAGAGCCCACCCAGAGGCCCCCGACCAUCUGUGAGCGCUGGAGGGAAAACCUGCUGGAGCACUACGGUGGCACCCCCCGGGAUGACCAGUACGUGCCCCAGUGCGAUGACCUGGGCCACUUCAUCCCCCUGCAGUGCCACGGAAAGAGCGACUUCUGCUGGUGUGUGGACAAAGAUGGCAGAGAGGUGCAGGGCACCCGCUCCCAGCCAGGCACCACCCCUGCGUGUAUACCCACCGUCGCUCCACCCAUGGUCCGGCCCACGCCCCGGCCAGAUGUGACCCCUCCAUCUGUGGGCACCUUCCUGCUCUAUACUCAGGGCCAGCAGAUUGGCUACUUACCCCUCAAUGGCACCAGGCUUCAGAAGGAUGCAGCUAAGACCCUGCUGUCUCUGCAUGGCUCCAUAAUCGUGGGAAUUGAUUACGACUGCCGGGAGAGGAUGGUGUACUGGACAGAUGUUGCUGGACGGACAAUCAGCCGUGCUGGUCUGGAACUGGGAGCAGAGCCUGAGACGAUCGUGAAUUCAGGUCUGAUAAGCCCUGAAGGACUUGCCAUAGACCACAUCCGCAGAACAAUGUACUGGACGGACAGUGUCCUGGAUAAGAUAGAGAGCGCCCUGCUGGAUGGCUCUGAGCGCAAGGUCCUCUUCUACACAGAUCUGGUGAAUCCCCGUGCCAUCGCUGUGGAUCCAAUCCGAGGCAACUUGUACUGGACAGACUGGAAUAGAGAAGCUCCUAAAAUUGAAACGUCAUCUUUAGAUGGAGAAAACAGAAGAAUUCUGAUCAAUACAGACAUUGGAUUGCCCAAUGGCUUAACCUUUGACCCUUUCUCUAAACUGCUCUGCUGGGCAGAUGCAGGAACCAAAAAACUGGAGUGUACACUACCUGAUGGAACUGGACGGCGUGUCAUUCAAAACAACCUCAAGUACCCCUUCAGCAUCGUAAGCUAUGCAGAUCACUUCUACCACACAGACUGGAGGAGGGAUGGUGUUGUAUCAGUAAAUAAACAUAGUGGCCAGUUUACUGAUGAGUAUCUCCCAGAACAACGAUCUCACCUCUACGGGAUAACUGCAGUCUACCCCUACUGCCCAACAGGAAGAAAGUAAGUACAGUAAUGUAAAGGAAGACUUGGAGUUUACAAUCAGAACCUGGACCCUAAAGAACAGUGACUGCAAAGGCAAAGAAAGUAAAAAAGGAAUUGGCCAUUAGACGUUCCUGAGCAUCCAAGAUGAACAUUUUGUAGUGCAAAAAGACUUUUGUGAAAAGCUGAUACCUCAAUCUUUACUACUGUAUUUUUAAAAAUGAAGGUUGUUAUUGCAAGUUUAAAAAGGUAACAGAAUUUUAACUGUUGCUUAUUAAAGCAACUUCUUGUAAACAUUUAUCAUUAAUAUUUAAAAGAUCAAAUUCAUUCAACUAAGAAUUAGAGUUUAAGACUCUAAACCUGAUUUUUGCCAUGGAUUCCUUCUGGCCAAGAAAUUAAAGCACAUGUGAUCAAUAUAACAAUAUAAUCCUAAACCUUGACAGUUGGAGAAGCCAAUGCAGAACUGAUGGGAAAGGACCAAUUAUUUAUAGUUUCCCAACAAAAGUUCUAAGAUUUUUUACCUCUGCAUCAGUGCAUUUCUAUUUAUAUCAAAAGGUGCUAAAAUGAUUCAAUUUGCAUUUUCUGAUCCUGUAGUGCCUCUAUAGAAGUACCCACAGAAAGUAAAGUAUCACAUUUAUAAAUACCAAAGAUGUAACAAUUUUAAAAUUUUCUAGAUUACUCCAAUAAAGUGUUUUAAGUUUU